GCAUAUUUGCUAAGAGCACCAUGCGCGCAGCAGCCAUCUCCACUCCAAAGUUAGACAAAAUGCCAGGAAUGUUCUUCUCUGCUAACCCAAAGGAAUUGAAAGGAACCACUCAUUCACUUCUAGACGACAAAAUGCAAAAAAGGAGGCCAAAGACUUUUGGAAUGGAUAUGAAAGCAUACCUGAGAUCUAUGAUCCCACAUCUGGAAUCUGGAAUGAAAUCUUCCAAGUCCAAGGAUGUACUUUCUGCUGCUGAAGUAAUGCAAUGGUCUCAAUCUCUGGAAAAACUUCUUGCCAACCAAACUGGUCAAAAUGUCUUUGGAAGUUUCCUAAAGUCUGAAUUCAGUGAGGAGAAUAUUGAGUUCUGGCUGGCUUGUGAAGACUAUAAGAAAACAGAGUCUGAUCUUUUGCCCUGUAAAGCAGAAGAGAUAUAUAAAGCAUUUGUGCAUUCAGAUGCUGCUAAACAAAUCAAUAUUGACUUCCGCACUCGAGAAUCUACAGCCAAGAAGAUUAAAGCACCAACCCCCACGUGUUUUGAUGAAGCACAAAAAGUCAUAUAUACUCUUAUGGAAAAGGACUCUUAUCCCAGGUUCCUCAAAUCAGAUAUUUACUUAAAUCUUCUAAAUGACCUGCAGGCUAAUAGCCUAAAGUGACUGGUCCCUGGCUGAAGGGAAUUAACAGAUAGUAUCAAGCGCAGAAGGAAUGUGCCAGUAUGGCUCCCUGGGUGAACAGCUUGGCCUUUUUUGGGUGUCUUGACAGGCCAAGAAGAACAAAUGACUCAGAAUGGAUUAACAUGAAAGUUAUCCAGGCGCAGAGUUGAAGAAGCAUAAGCAAGACAAAAACAGAGAGACCGCAGAAGGAGGAAGAUACUGUGGUACUGUCAUAAAAAACAGUGGAGCUCUGUAUUAGAAAGCCCCUCAGAACUGGGAAGGCCAGGUAACUCUAGUUACACAGAAACUGUGACUAAAGUCUAUGAAACUGAUUACAACAGACUGUAAGAAUCAAAGUCAACUGACAUCUAUGCUACAUAUUAUUAUAUAGUUUGUACUGAGCUAUUGAAGUCCCAUUAACUUAAAGUAUAUGUUUUCAAAUUGCCAUUGCUACUAUUGCUUGUCGGUGUUAUUUUAUUUUAUUGUUUUUGACUUUGGAAGAGAUGAACUGUGUAUUUAACUUAAGCUAUUGCUCUUAAAACCAGGGAGUCAGAAUAUAUUUGUAAGUUAAAUCAUUGGUGCUAAUAAUAAAUGUGGAUUUUGUAUUAAAAUAUAUAGAAGCAAUUUCUGUUUACAUGUCCUUGCUACUUUUAAAAACUUGCAUUUAUUCCUCAGAUUUUAAAAAUAAAUAAAUAAUUCAUUUAA